AGGCUCCUGGGGUGGAGUCCAAAUCACUCAUUGUUUGUGAAAGCUGAGCUCACAGCAAAACAAGCCACCAUGAAGCUGUCGGUGUGUCUCCUGCUGGUCACGCUGGCCCUCUGCUGCUACCAGGCCAAUGCCGAGUUCUGCCCAGCUCUUGUUUCUGAGCUGUUAGACUUCUUCUUCAUUAGUGAACCUCUGUUCAAGUUAAGUCUUGCCAAAUUUGAUGCCCCUCCGGAAGCUGUUGCAGCCAAGUUAGGAGUGAAGAGAUGCACGGAUCAGAUGUCCCUUCAGAAACGAAGCCUCAUUGCGGAAGUCCUGGUGAAAAUAUUGAAGAAAUGUAGUGUGUGACAUGUAAAAACUUUCAUCCUGGUUUCCACUGUCUUUCAAUGACACCCUGAUCUUCACUGCAGAAUGUAAAGGUUUCAACGUCUUGCUUUAAUAAAUCACUUGCUCUCCACGUC